AGUGCGGUGUUUGUCUGCCGGACUGACGGGCGGCCGGGCGGUGCGCGGCGGCGGUGGCGGCGGGGAAGAUGGCGGCGUCCUCCCUGGAACAGAAGCUGUCCCGCCUGGAAGCAAAGCUGAAGCAGGAGAACCGGGAGGCCCGGCGGAGGAUCGACCUCAACCUGGAUAUCAGCCCCCAGCGGCCCAGGCCCAUUAUUGUGAUCACUCUAAGCCCUGCUCCUGCCCCGUCCCAACGAGCAGCCCUGCAGCUCCCGCUGGCCAACGAUGGGGGCAGCCGCUCGCCAUCCUCAGAGAGCUCCCCGCAGCACCCCACGCCCCCCGCCCGGCCCCGCCACAUGCUGGGGCUCCCGUCAACCCUGUUCACACCCCGCAGCAUGGAGAGCAUUGAGAUUGACCAGAAGCUGCAGGAGAUCAUGAAGCAGACGGGCUACCUGACCAUCGGGGGCCAGCGCUACCAGGCAGAAAUCAACGACCUGGAGAACUUGGGCGAGAUGGGCAGCGGCACCUGCGGCCAGGUGUGGAAGAUGCGCUUCCGGAAGACCGGCCACGUCAUUGCCGUUAAGCAAAUGCGGCGCUCCGGGAACAAGGAGGAGAACAAGCGCAUCCUCAUGGACCUGGAUGUGGUGCUGAAGAGCCACGACUGCCCCUACAUCGUGCAGUGCUUUGGGACGUUCAUCACCAACACGGACGUCUUCAUCGCCAUGGAGCUCAUGGGCACCUGCGCUGAGAAGCUCAAGAAGCGGAUGCAGGGCCCCAUCCCCGAGCGCAUUCUGGGCAAGAUGACAGUGGCGAUUGUGAAGGCGCUGUACUACCUGAAGGAGAAGCACGGUGUCAUCCACCGCGACGUCAAGCCCUCCAACAUCCUGCUGGACGAGCGGGGCCAGAUCAAGCUCUGCGACUUCGGCAUCAGCGGCCGCCUGGUGGACUCCAAAGCCAAGACGCGGAGCGCCGGCUGUGCCGCCUACAUGGCACCCGAGCGCAUUGACCCCCCAGACCCCACCAAGCCGGACUAUGACAUCCGGGCCGACGUAUGGAGCCUGGGCAUCUCGUUGCCCUGCCCGUCUCCCUCCCAGGUGGAGCUGGCAACAGGACAGUUUCCCUACAAGAACUGCAAGACGGACUUUGAGGUCCUCACCAAAGUCCUACAGGAAGAGCCCCCGCUUCUGCCCGGACACAUGGGCUUCUCGGGGGACUUCCAGUCCUUCGUCAAAGACUGCCUUACUAAAGAUCACAGGAAGAGACCAAAGUAUAAUAAGCUACUUGAACACAGCUUCAUCAAGCGCUACGAGACGCUGGAGGUGGACGUGGCGUCCUGGUUCAAGGAUGUCAUGGCGAAGACUGAGUCACCGCGGACUAGCGGCGUCCUGAGCCAGCCCCACCUGCCCUUCUUCAGGUAGCUGCUUGGCGGCGGCCAGCCCCACAGGGGGCCAGGGGCAUGGCCACAGGCCCCCCUCCCCACUUGGCCACCCAGCUGCCUGCCAGGGGAGACCUGGGACCUGGACGGCCACCUAGGACUGAGGACAGAGAGUGGGGGGUGCCCACCCACCCCCCCCGCCCCGGGCCUACCAAGCCCCCGCCCUUCCCACCCCGGGGUCAGCCGGCCGUGUGCGUCCCCCGACAGACACUGUGAACGGAAGACAGCAGGCCGCGAUCAGAGUCGCUGUUCAUUCAGCCGCAGCCUCUGGGCCGGGGCGGCCCCCAGGGGCCAGGAGAGAGCCCUGGAGUCCCGCAGCCACCAUGCACGCUCCCAGCGUGCUGUGUCCUUCGCCACUCCCACGCGCCCGUUCCUCUUCCGUCGCCCUCUGUCCCCUGCUCUACCUCUCUGUCCUUGUCUGGCUCUCCCGUCACCCUCCCUGCCUCUGUCUCUCUUCUGGCCUGAGCCUGGGCCCAGCCACCUCCUGACGGGUCCCCUGGGUCUGCAUAGGUCUCCCAUGGCGCAAUGAGUCAGUGGCCCCCAGCCAGGCAGUGUGGGCAUUGCCACUGCGGCUGGACGGGGCUGCGCGCUCGCGCUCUCUCUCUCUCUCUCUCUCUCUCUUUGAUCUCAGGGGGUCCUUUUUGGAGUUUAUUGUAUUUUAUUGUACUUGGUGGGGUGUUUGGGGUGGGGGCGGAGGAGAGCUUGUUCUCGUGGGGUUGUCGGUACCUUCAGAAACUUUUACCAAAGUCACGAUUAGCUGCUUGUGGUGGGGCCCCAACCGCCCUCGGGCACUGGGGAGCUGGGCUGGGGCUGCUGCUCUGGGGUCUCCGGGGGCCACAGCUUGGGGUGAGUUGAAGACCUCAGGGGAUGUGGAGGGGUCUGCGGGGCCCUGGCCGCACAGGAUGGCCUUCAGGGAAGGUGGUCUUGGGGCAUGGUGCAGAGCAGGUGACCGGAGGGAAUCGGUGACGGAGCGGGGCCAAGGGAGGGGUCCGGAGGGAGUCAGGGAUGGAGGGCAGAGGGAGUGGAUGUGGGGGUUUGAGGACGUGUGACAAGCUCCAGCAGGGGUGGGGGCCGGGCUGAGGGUGGGGGUGCGAGGUGGUCACUCCCAUCGUGCCCCUGGCCGUCCCUCCACUCACCCACACCUGGCCCAGUCCACGUUGAGGUCCAGGACUGGGAAGGACCGGGUGAGUGCACCGGGGACCCAGGCCAGGUGCCCCCCGGAGCCUGCUGGGGUGGCCAGAGCAGGAGGGGGUGUGUUUCCUUUUUGUGGGUGUUGCAUGCAAAUCAAGUGGACAAGAAAAAAUAACAAAACAAAAAACAAGAAAAAAAAAACACAAAACCCCGUAAAAUCACAAAGAAAAUCCAACACCAAAGGCGCAGAAGCCGGCUGGCCGUGGUGGGGGCAGCGUAGGCGUAGCAUCCCUCUCCUCUCACUUAGCCUGUUGACUCUUGUUAUUAUCAUGAUAUUCACAAAACGCCGCAUGUUUAAAAAGUCAUAGAUGUCAUCUUCUCUCUGCCCCCAGGGAGGAAAGCCACCUUCUCUUGCCCCUUGGCCCCUUUGUCAGGGGCCAGGGGUCUGCCGGGUGGGGGUGCCAACAGGCCUGGCCCUUUCCUCCCCUGCAUCCAGCCAUGGGGGCCUCUGCGAUUGCCGGAAGGUUGCAUGGCUGGUCCCAGGGCCAGCACAGGCCCGAGGCCGGGCUGCCUGGUUUUAUUUUUAUUUAACUUUAUUUUCUGUUUUAUGAGUGUGUGUCCGCCCACCCCCACCCCCUUCAGUGUUAAGUGGGGAGCCCUGGGGGAGUCUCUCCUGCCUCCCAGCCUCUCCCAAGACCUCCCCCCUCGUCACCAGCCAUCCCUCUGGACCAGGCAGAGGGCGGACCGGGUGGGCAGGGGCCUGAGGGUGGCUCGGGCCAGCCCACCAGCCAAUGGACCCCUCCUCAGGCCGCCAGUGUCGCCCUGCCCCUUUUUAAAACAAAAUGCCCUCGUUUGUAAACCCUUAGACGCUUGAGAAUAAACCCCUUCCUUUUCUUCCA